UUUCUUUUCUUUUUUUUUUUUUUUUUUUUUUUGAGAUGGAGUCUCGCUCUAUCGCCCAGGCUGGAGUGCAGUGGCGCGAUCUUGGCUCACUGCCAUCUCUGCCUCCUGGGUUCACGCCAUUCUGCCUCAGCCUCCAGAGCAGCUGGGACCACAGGCGCCCGCCACCACACCUGGCUAAUUUUGCUUUGUAUUUUCAGUAGAGACGGGGUUUCACCAUGUUAGCCAGGAUGGUCUCGAUCUCCUGACCUCGUGAUCCGCCCACUUCGGCCUCCCAAAGUGCUGGGAUUACAGGCAUGAGCCACUGCGCCCGGCCUACUCUACACUUUUUUUAACCCUAAGAAUUACCACUACAGUAAUGUAGUGGAGUGGGAAGAGUGCCUGGAAUCAGAAGACCCUGUUGAGGCUGAAUUUAGCUGUAUGACCUCAUGCAAGCCAUUUAAACUCUGUGCCUCAGCGUCCUCAUUUUUAAAAGGAGGUUUGAUCUCUAUGUUUACUUCCAGCUCUGAUUCUGGGAUUCUAAUCCACAGGACUUGGGUGUUAGGGUGGAACCUAGAACUGUGCUGUCCAGUGCAGUAGCCACUAGCCACAUGUGGCUACUGAGCACUUGCAAUGUGGCUAGUACAAAGUGAGAUGUGCUAUCAAUGUAAGAUACAUACCAGAUUUUGAAGACUAGUAUUACCAAAAGAAUGUAAAAUAUCACAUUAAUAAUUUUAUAUUAAUUACAUGUUCAAAUGAUAUUUUGGAUAUACUGAAUUAAAACAUUAAAAUUAGUUCUACUUGUAUCUUUUUACUUUUUUAAUGUGGCUAGAAGAAAAUAAAAUUAUACAUGUGGCUCAGAUUAUAUUUCUAUUGGACAGCGCUGCUCUAGAACAUUAUAUUAAGUGGUUAUUAUUGAAGUAGACCAAAGUUUAUACCAUAAGGAUAUUUUUCCUUAAAUACCAUGUUUGAAGAACAAUUAUUUAUUGAUCCUUGAAUCUGUAAGAUCAAAUAACAAGUCUCUAUCCAUGUUACCAAAUUUAAACUUUUGAAAAUAAUAAACUUUAAAAUAUCAGAUGUGUUAUUACAGGAUGAUACUUGGAAUCAAGUGAAAUGAGUUAUAUGGUCAUCACUAAAUUUAGAAAUCUAUUGUGAAACAAAGACAAACAGGAAAGUACAGAAUAGAGACUUUUAGUAAAUAAAUGGAAUUUAAAAGAAAGUGUUUAUUUACAGUGUCACGACAGAAAAGGAUGUCUUUGUUGUCAUAGUCUUUGAGGGAUCUCCGUAAAAUCUGGGGCACAGGUACAAGAAAUAGCCAAUAUUUAGUUCCCAGACCAUGUUUAGUAGUGUCCAGUUUCAGAUCAUGCUGCCAAGAGGUAUCUCCCCCUCAGGUGGGUCAUCACUGAGCCCUGGAAUUGGAGACUCAUACUUGCCCAGCACAAUGUUACGGGCAGACAGGCCGACAUCUAUGAUUAGCUAGAAGCCAUAAAGAAAAGCUGCUAAGUGGCCACUAGGUGCCACUUUUCUGUUUUUGUAAUGCUUUCAUUAGCAGAUCUUUUUUUUCCAAGCUCCAUGGGGCCUAUGAGAGGCAUUUAUGAUUUUUGUGCCUACAAUAAGUCAGCCUGUCUGGUGUGAGUUGUUUUAUGAGAAAUGCUUUCCAAGGGAGGUCUAGGAAGAUCCUGACACAUAAGAACUUUGGCUUAGAGAGCUUUCCAGGUGUAGUGCCAAUAAAAACUGACCUGGAAAGAAAACCUGCCCAGCACGGAACAUGCUUUCUGAACUCACUUGAGAGUGUAUGGUGUAUGUCACUUCUCAUAUAUUCUUGAGUUUAGAUUUGUCUUUUAUACAAUUUUUAGCUCUUUUCCAGUUCACUUGUGCUCGUCUGUAUAUUGGUAUUUUUAAAUUUUUGUGGUAAAUAAUGAAAAGAGUGAAAUUAUAUUUUAUAAUUACUCAUUUGUAGUUUUUUUUUUUAAUUUAAUAAACUUCCUCCAAAAAGUGCUCCCUUAACUACUUUCUAAUGUGGAAACAUAGAUUAAGGAAACCAUCCAGUGCCCUCAAACCACUGGGCAGAGGGGUACAUUGAACUCUGUUACUAUAUAUAUUUCUGGGUAUGUUCCCCAGGGUAUACUAACUGCUGUAACAACUCCAAAAUCUCAGUGGUUUAACCAGUAAAGGUUUCCUUGUGCUCACGUCAGACUCCAACGUCAUCAGCCUUAUCUGUCCCUCUGACUCUCUCCUCCUCCCUUUCUGCCUCUUCCUCAUUCCAUCCCUCAGCUUUGCUUUCCUAUGAGCUGGUUUUAUCUUCCGGUGGACCCUCUCCGCAUAAUGACACUCAGAAGUUCCAAGCGUAUAUUGUUCUUAUACCUGACAAUUUCAGUGGAAAGAGAGCCUCUCUAUUUCCUAGUAAUUCACAUGCACAUAUGCAUUGACUGGGCCUCUGGAUCAACUUGGUUUACCUGGACUUUCUGUUGUGUGGUUGCAGUAUCUACACUAAUUCUAGAGAGUCAACCAUCAUGAAUUAUAAGGUUCUAUUGUCCCUUCUGCAGAUAACCCUGUCCUCCCUCAGGCCCCAGGCUGUCUAGCUGUUGGCAUCUGACAUCUUUUCCCCUUCAAGGAUGCCUUUAAAGUUUAUUUUAAUUUAUUUAAUCAGAAUUAAAAUGUUAGGAAGGGAAGGCAAAAUAAGCAGUAGGUUCUUUCCAGGUCAACAGCCUGGAAUAUACAGAUUAGCCAGGCUGUGAUACAUGCUCAACCUUGGGUUGAAGUUUGGCGAGGCAGCCCUGUUGGAAUCUGGGGAUCUCCCAUGGGGAUCUUCCAACACACUGGACUCUCCUCUUCCCCAGGUCUCCCACUGCCAGCACAAGAGGCUGUGAAGGUGAAGAGGAUACAGAUUUAAGAGAUUUGUAUUACAGAAGUAGGAUGGCAAGAACUUGAGGACCAAUUGCAUAUGGGAAAUGUUGAAGCAAAAGCAGUGAACAAUGACUCAAGUUUCUGGCCCCAGGGGUCUGGAUUGCAGUGCUGUUCAAGAGGGUAUGUUGGAGCUAGAGGCUGAGCAUGACCAGGACCUGAGUAAACAGGAUAAGCAAGAAACAGAUGUUGAUGAGGACCCUCAAGCGUCUACAUCUCUGCAGUUUUCAAAGAAGAACCUCCUUGAACUGUGUCUGAAGGGCAUGUUCCUCAAGCUAAACUACUGGAACACAAAGAUAGGUCUCCAGGUGAAAGAACUUGGAGCUGAUUACAUAGACGGAACGGAGAAAAUUGACAAUAUUAUUAAAAAAAUAAAUGUAACAGAAAACACAGUGAAGAGCUUAUUAAAAGACAUGCUGACCCUGAAGGGUCAAAUUGAAAAGCUGGAGGACCGGGGCCUUGACCUUGAUCAAGGGACAAGCACUGAGGUGAAUACUUGUAAUGAAGUUUAUGAAUUAAAGAAGAAAGUCAUAGAAAGGCUGGAGGACCUUUGCAAGAAUGUGGAACUGCUGAGUGCAAAGCUAAGGAUGUAUCAAAUGGAGGCAGAGGACACUGACUCUCACAGUUCUGAGGAAAUAGAUACGGAAGAGAUGGAGGCCCUGCUUCCUCAGGCCCCAGCAUCCUUUUUAGUGCAGAAGUCUCCUCCCCGCAAUACAGCAUGGAAACGUGCACUGAGGAUUUUCAUCAUGUUUGAUGUCCUCACCGUCACUGGACUUUUAUGUUACAUACUAUUUUUUGGUGCUACAUUUCUCUUUGAAAGGGUGCUUCUGAGAAUGCUUGGGUGCCGCACCACAUGGGACCUACGGGAGAUGAGAGAGCCUUUCUUGAAUUUGGAAGUGGAAGCCUUGUUACCCUCCUAAAGAUACAGAAGUUACUGUCACCCUACUGACUUUCUCACCAGUAAACAUUGUGGCUGUUCCUGUA